AUUGUCAGCUGCGUUUCCGCGGUCGCGGGUGAGUGUGCCCGGGCUAGCGGCCUGGGUUGGGCUUUGUAGCUGCUCCGCAGGCCCAGCCCGGGCCGCGCUCGCAGAGUCCUAGGCGGUGCGCGGCCUCCUGCCUCCUCCCUCCUCGGCGGUCGCGGCCCGCCGGCCUCCGCGGUGCCUGCCUUCGCUCUCAGGUUGAGGAGCUCAAGCUUGGGAAAAUGGUGUGCAUUCCUUGUAUCGUCAUUCCAGUUCUGCUCUGGAUCUACAAAAAAUUCCUGGAGCCAUAUAUAUACCCUCUGGUUUCCCCCUUCGUUAGUCGUAUAUGGCCUAAGAAAGCAAUACAAGAAUCCAAUGAUACAAACAAAGGCAAAGUAAACUUUAAGGGUGCAGACAUGAAUGGAUUACCAACAAAAGGACCAACAGAAAUCUGUGAUAAAAAGAAAGACUAAAGAAAUUUUCCUAAAGGACCCCAUCAUUUAAAAAAUGGACCUGAUAAUAUGAAGCAUCUUCCUUGUAAUUGUCUCUGACCUUUUUAUCUGAGACCGGAAUUCAGGAUAGGAGUCUAGAUAUUUACCUGAUACUAAUCAGGAAAUAUAUGAUAUCCGUAUUUAAAAUGUAGUUAGUUAUAUUUAAUGACCUCAUUCCUAAGUUCCUUUUUCGUUAAUGUAGCUUUCAUUUCUGUUAUUGCUGUUUGAAUAAUAUGAUUAAAUAGAAGGUUUGUGCCAGUAGACAUUAUGUUACUAAAUCAGCACUUUAAAAUCUUUGGUUCUCUAAUUCAUAUGAAUUUGCUGUUUGCUCUAAUUUCUUUGGGCUCUUCUAAUUUGAGUGGAGUACAAUUUUGUUGUGAAACAGUCCAGUGAAACUGUGCAGGGAAAUGAAGGUAGAAUUUUGGGAGGUAAUAAUGAUGUGAAACAUAAAGAUUUAAUAAUUACUGUCCAACACAGUGGAGCAGCUUGUCCACAAAUAUAGUAAUUACUAUUUAUUGCUCUAAGGAAGAUUAAAAAAAGAUAGGGAAAAGGGGGAAACUUCUUUGAAAAAUGAAACAUCUGUUACAUUAAUGUCUAAUUAUAAAAUUUUAAUCCUUACUGCAUUUCUUCUGUUCCUACAAAUGUAUUAAACAUUCAGUUUAACUGGUAGUUCAUUUUCUUUUAAAGUCUAUUGAAAUAUUCAAAAGGGAAAUUUUUCACCACGUCAGAAGGCAGAAUUUGGAUGUUGUGAUGGCAUCUGUGUAGUGGUGGGACAACAAUUACUAUUGUUGCGUAACAAGACACUCCAAAAUUUAGUGGUUUUCAGCAGCAGUGACUCGACUGGGCAGUUCUUUGCUGUUCUGGGCUCACUCAUAUGGCUGGCUGGGCCUGGGUCUGGACCUGGGCCGCUAUGUGAUUUUUAUCUUGGGCUUUGAAAAUUCAGUGUAGGGACCUAUAAAUAUUCAAAGAUGAUGAGAUGCAUCCUUAUAUAUUUUUUGUAUUCACUCUGAAGCUGGGAAAGAUUAAAAGGAACUCCUGCCCUUGGGUCCCUAAUGAAGUCUGGGUCCUAACUCAGGCUCUAUUAAGUUCUGUGGCUGGUCAAGUCACUGAUUUACCUUGGGCUUUAUUUGAUAUAAAUCAUGUAAAUCAGCAGGUCUCAGCUUUUCUGUCCAAAGCCACCUGAGGGAUAAGAUAAAUUCUCAUUAGCAAAUAAACUUUUUUAAGGUAUAAAUACUAUUAUAAAAAUAACAGAUAUUUACAGUACAACAAUGCAAGAGGAUCCUAAAUGAAAAGCGAAUGUUUUUUCUCAACUCUCAUUCCCUUAUUCCAGCUCCACAGAGGUAACCAAUUGUUUUUUUGUUGUUGUUGUUGUAUGGUUUGUUUUUGUUAGACAGUAGUCUUUUCCUGAACAGUGCUGCUCCUUGUGGAGCAAGGCUAAUUCAUAGGCAGUGCAUCCAGAGUCCGCCCCAGUUGAUUUUGUGUGUAACCUUCUAGCAACUUUUUGAAAAUUAAUUUGUUCUUAAAUAUGCACAUCAUUUUUAUUUAUUUAUGUUUUUGAGACAGGGUCUCACUCUGUCACUCAAGCUGGAGUGCAGCAGCAUGAUCACGGCUCUCUAUGGCCUCGACCUGCAGUCCUGAAGUGAUCCUCUCACCUUAGCCUCUCAAGUAGCUGGGACUACAGGUGCACACCACCAUGCCCAGCUAAUGUUUUUUGUAAUUUUUUUUAUAGAGACAGGGUUUCGUCAUGUUGCCUGGGCUGAUCUCGAUCUCCUGGGCUCAAGCGAUCCUCCACUUUGGCUUCCCAAAGUGCUGGGAUUACAGGCAUGAGCUACUACUGCACCUGGCCCACACAUCAUCUUUUAAAAAUUAAGUAAUAUUGCAACGUUUCUAAUUGUCCCUACUUCUUUGCUCCUCAAAGGUUUUACCUACUGAGCUGUGGGCUUUUUAAAUUUAUCUCCAUAUUUAUAAAUAAAUUAUAAAAAUAUAAAAAUAUAAACAUUUUAUUUUUUGAGACAGGGUCUCACUGUCACCCAGGUGCUGGAGUGCAGCGGCAUCAUCAUAGCUCACUACAGCCUCCAACUCCUGGGCUCAAGUGAUCCUCCCACCUCAGCCUCCUGAAUUGCUAGGACUACAGGUGUGUGCCACCACGCCUGGCUAAUUUUUUGUAGAGACGGGGUCUUGCUCUGUUGCCCAAGCGAGUCUCAAACUCCUGGCCUCAAAGUGAUCCUCUUGCCUCAGCCUCCCAAAGUGUCGGGAUUACAGGCAUGAGCCACUGCCUGGCUAUACUGUUAUAUUUUGAGCCAUCAACUUCAGACAUUGUUUCCCAUAAUGGUUGAGAUGCCGCUAUCUUACACUGCCUCUGCUCCUCCCACACAUCCUCCCAAGUGCUUUUGUAAAUUUUGCUUACAUCAUCAGUGUUCAUAGCAUGAGUGUGCCAGGUGUCUUUCAUUUGCCCCUCCCAAGUCUCUGCUCCCCUCAUCCUGCUUUCAGCCCAAGGAAGCUGUAUAGACAUCAACAGACUUCCCAUGUCUCUGGGUUCUGCUGGGUUUGGCCAAUAGCGAUCCAUAGCAGGAGAUGGCUGGAGGGAGGAGAAUGAAGGCAGAGUGUUUAUUCCCUUGGCCCUCUCUCUGCAAGGUCACCUCAGGCCAACUGUUCCUCAGCCAGAAGUCACUGUGCCUCAAGGAACACUCCAGGCAGCCAACUCCACCUGACUUCUUUUAUUUUUCCUAACCUGUCCUUCACCCUGCCCUUUUGGGCCCAGGGGUGGUGGUAUUUCUGUUACUGGCUCUGGGCUACUGCUUCCUCUCAAGAGUGCUAUCUGGCUUGCUGGGACACUGCCUGGGAGAAUACUAUUGCUCACUGCACAGGUUAAUGCACUGUGAUUGCGUCCCUUUUAAUAUACAGGUGGUGUCUUCCUGGAGUGACCAGUUUACCUUCUCCCCAUACACCUCUCCUGCCUAGUUGUUGCCUAGACCUGGUGCACACUGCAGUCCUCGGGACUUUCUGUUGCCACCCUCCUGUAUUGGACGUCUUGUUUCUGGAUUUCCUAUCCUCUUCCUUCUUGGUUUAUCCCUCAUUUUUUCUGUAGCACAGCAGUUUUCUAAUUCAAUACUUUUAGGAGGUUGAGUAUGGAUAAUUUUGGAAAGUGUCCCCGGGAUGAUUCCAAUUUAUUUAAGCCUGUUUUCCAGAGAGCUGCGGGUCUCCUAAGGCCUUUCUCAUUUCUAACAAGUCUCCCUCUCUAGAACACUGGUUCCCAGUCGUUGUUUUCAUACUAGCAACAUUUUAAAAGCAGGAUAGGGGUGGCUAGUAUGCAAUUGCCAACUUUUGAUUUUUCCAAGCAGGAGUAUAUCAAAAAGCUACAAUUUAUUACCAGUAUUUCGUAAAAGACAGUUUGACACCAGAAGAGUGAAAAAGAACAUGGGAAUAGUGGACAAAAAUAGCCAUCAGUUUGAAUAAGCGUAUGAAAAGUGUUAAUUUUAUGAAAAAUUCACUAUUUUGUUCAUAUUUUUCUUAUUUUGGAGGCUAAUUGUUAAAAGCUUUUAUCAGUUAUCCAUGGGCUGGAGUUGGUAGCCACUGUUUGAUACCACACAAAUGUUUCUUUGCCCUAAAAUAUCAACAUCUGUCUGUGUAAAGGUCAGGGCUGCCUUUUUAGUAAGAGCUACCCUUUGUUAAACACAUUGUACCUGCACUGUUCAUGGGUGUUUCACACACACAAACCUACCUGGUCUGCAUAAACCUGAAAUACAGUCAAGAAAACAGGAUCCACCGGAGGCGGUGACUCAAGCCUAUAAUCCCAGCACUUUGGGAGGCCGAGGUGGGAGGAUCACUUGAGGCCGGGAGUUCAAGACCAGCCUGGCCAACAUGGUGAAACCCUGUCUCUACUAAAAAUACAAAAAUUAGUCGGGCAUAGUGGUACACACCUGUAAUCCCAGCUACUCCAGAGGCUGAGGCAUGAGAAUCGUUUGAAACCAGGAGGCAGAGGUUGCAGUGAGCUGAAAUUGUACCACUGCACUCCAGCCUAGGUGACAGAGCAAGACUGUCUCAAAAGAAAAGAAAAAGAAAAACAGGAUCCCAGCCUGGGCAACAUAGGGAGACCUCGCCUCCACCAAAAAUUAAAAAAUUUAGCUAGGCAUAUGGUGAUGUGCACCUGUGGUCCCAGCUACUCUGGAGGCUGAGGUGGGAGGAUUGCUUGAACCCAGGAGGUUAAAGGCUACAGUGAGCUGUGAUCAAGCCACUGCACUCUAGCUUGGACAACAGAGCAAGACCCUGUCUUAAAAAAAGAAAAAAAGAAUAAUGGAGUUUAAAUAUGUAAAUGACAAGUCUAAGAUUUCAAGGUCAUACUUUCAUGCUAAGGAGCCAUCACAGCUACAUAUAUAUAUAGUGUAUAUAUAUAUAUAGUGUGUAUAUAUAUAUAGUGUAUAUACAUAUAGUGUAUAUAUAUAUAGUGUAUAUAUAUAGUGUGUAUAUAUAUAGUGUGUGUAUAUAUAUAUAUGUGUAUAUAUAUAUAGUGUGUGUAUAUAUAUAUAUUUUUGUUUGUUUGUUUGUUUUUGGAAGAUGGAGUUUCGCUCUUGUUGCCCAGGCUGCAGUGCAAUGGUGCAAUCUCUGCUCACCACAACCUCCUCCUCCCAGGUUCAAGCGAUUCUGCCUCAGCCUCCCAAGUAGCUGGGAUUACAGGUGCGUGCUACCACACCCGGCUAAUUUUGUACUUUAGUAGAGACGGGGUUUCACCACGUUGGUCAGGCUGGUCUCAAACUCCCAACCUCCAGUGAUCUGCCUGCCUUGGCCUCCCAAAGUGCUGGGAUCACAGGCAUAAGCACUGGGCCCGGCUGCCACAGCUACUAAUAUCUUAAUUGUUAGUAAUACCUUAUUGGGAAUAAUUAGGCAGAAAUGGAGAGGGUGAGUUUAGAUUAAUCAGUAUGUGUGAACUUGUUUUAAAGUUUCUGGAGGCUGAGGUGAGAGGAUCGCUUAAGUCCAGGAGGCGGAAGUUGCAGUGAGCCAAGAUCACACCACUGUACUCCAGCCAGGACAACAGAGCAAUACCCCGUUUCAAAUAAAUAAUAAUAAAGUUAAUUUUGCUAACCUUG